GGCAACAACAGCUAGACUCCGUCUCAAAAAAAAAAAAAAAGCCUUCUAUCUUUGAAUUUACAGAGUAAAACAGUUGCUGAACACGGAGCGAUGAAGAUGAGUGCCUGUAACAGUGUUAGCUUUUUCCAGUAUUGAUGAUUCCCCCGCCCCUCUUUUUUUUGUUUGUUUUUUUGUUUUUGUUUUUUGCUAUCCACCAUUUUUCUCUUCCCCCUCCUUCCUAGCCUUCGUGUUUCAUUUUAGGACUUUGGCUCUUAUAGGGGACUUGAACCAAAUGUUACUUAAAACCUGGAACAAGUUGAACUGGAACCAUAUUUACUCGACUUUGAAUCAAAUCUAAGUGCUUAAAAAUGUCCUUGGCAAACCACUUUCAUCUGAAACAGUAUAUUUUCUGAAAAGUUUUGAGCCUGGACAUCUGAUUCUCUGACUCUUAUGACUGUGGAUUAUAAGUUCACAUGUUGACCAUCUAAUAUGAGGCAGGCAUGGACUAGGUGCCAGGUAUAAUACAGAGGUGAAGAGGACAUGGUACCUGCCCUUUAGCGCCCCUCAUUGGUGGGGGAGGGAGCACACCUGGACAUAUCACAGUACAAGGUGUAGCAGAUUUCUCCACUGGGGUGCAAAGUAGACACCACUGAAAUGUCACUCAGUAGAUGUCAUUUCAGUUGGGUUUUGAGAUAAGCAGAAGUUAAGAACAUGAAGGAAUAUUUUCAUGUGGAGCGUAUGUGCUGAGGAAUGAAGGCAUUCAUGCGUUUGGGAUACAUCAGGAUGAUCACUAUAUCUGGAACAGAGUGAUAUGAGAUAAAUCUAUUAAGAUACUCAGUAGUGUGGAGAUUGAAGAGAAGCUAUUGGUUUUGGCAUCCUCAAAGUUCGUGAAAACCGAGUAAAGUGUUUUUGGUAGAGUGUUGGUGGAAGGGGCUGGAUUGCAGGGAGUUGAAGAGUGAAUGGAAACUGAGAACAGAAAGGUUAGACUCUUCAGGAAGUUUGUCCUGAGAAGGAAAUAGAGAAGGUGCCUGAGGAAGAGAGGGCUGGGGAGGGAUCUGUGUUGCAUCACAAGCGCGUGGAAGGAUGUGGGUGACUUUACUGUUUACAGGUGGAGGGAACAUAGCUAUGGACAGGGAAACUCAUGAAGAAGGGAGUAGGAUCAGAAACAGACUGGAGGAUAGGAAAAGGAGGGGUGCCUUUUCUGAAGACCAGUCGAAUGGAUGCGUGAAGCUAAAAAUGCUUAGAGGUCAAGGGAAGGAAGAAAGGUAAAGUGGCCCAUGGCCAGUGACCGCUGUUUUUUCACUUACUAAAUAUUGAGCCUCUGCUCUAGUUCAUAUCUAUUAGUGGUCGGUAAAGUAUUCUGAAAAGGUUGUCUAGCUUGUGGGUGACUUUAUUUUUUUUUGAGGUUGGAGCAAAAGUUUAAUAAGUGAAAGAAGAAAGCUCUCUGCUGCAGAGAGGGGACCUGGAAGAGCGUUGCCCUGGUUAUUCAGCUUCUCAAGGCUGGAAAAGCGAAGGAAGUUUCCUACAAUGCACUAGCCUCACACAUAAUCUCAGAGGAUGGGGACAAUCCAGAGGUGGGAGAAGCUCGGGAAGUCUUUGACUUACCUGUUGUAAAGCCUUCUUGGGUGAUUCUGUCCGUUCAGUGUGGAACUCUUCUGCCAGUAAAUGGUUUUUCUCCAGAAUCAUGUCAGAUUUUUUUUGGAAUCACUGCCUGCCUUUCUCAGGUGUCAUCUGAAGACAGAAGUGCCCUGUGGGCUUUGGUUACGUUCUAUGGGGGAGAUUGCCAGCUAACCCUCAAUAAGAAAUGCACGCAUUUGAUUGUUCCAGAGCCAAAGGGGGAGAAAUACGAAUGUGCUUUAAAGCGAGCAAGUAUUAAAAUUGUGACUCCUGACUGGGUUCUGGAUUGCGUAUCAGAGAAAACCAAAAAGGACGAAGCAUUUUAUCAUCCUCGUCUGAUUAUUUAUGAAGAGGAAGAAGAGGAAGAGGAAGAGGAGGAGGAAGUAGAAAAUGAGGAACAAGAUUCUCAGAAUGAGGGUAGUACAGAUGAGAAGUCAAGCCCUGCCAGCUCUCAAGAAGGGUCUCCUUCAGGUGACCAGCAGUUUUCACCUAAAUCCAACACUGAAAAAUCUAAAGGGGAAUUAAUGUUUGAUGAUUCUUCAGAUUCAUCACCGGAAAAACAGGAGAGAAAUUUAAACUGGACCCCGGCCGAAGUCCCACAGUUAGCUGCAGCAAAACGCAGGCUGCCUCAGGGAAAGGAGCCUGGGUUGAUUAACUUGUGUGCCAAUGUCCCACCCGUCCCAGGUAACAUUUUGCCCCCUGAGGUCCGGGGUAAUUUAAUGGCUGCUGGACAAAACCUCCAAAGUUCUGAAAGAUCAGAAAUGAUAGCUACCUGGAGUCCAGCUGUACGGACACUGAGGAAUAUUACUAAUAAUGCUGACAUUCAGCAGAUGAACCGGCCAUCAAAUGUAGCACAUAUCUUACAGACUCUUUCAGCACCUACGAAAAAUUUAGAACAGCAGGUGAAUCACAGCCAGCAGGGACAUACAAAUGCCAAUGCAGUGCUGUUUAGCCAAGUGAAAGUGACUCCAGAGACACACAUGCUACAGCAGCAGCAGCAGGCCCAGCAGCAGCAGCAGCAGCACCCGGUUUUACACCUUCAGCCCCAGCAGAUAAUGCAGCUCCAGCAGCAGCAGCAGCAGCAGAUCUCUCAGCAACCUUACCCCCAGCAGCCGCCGCAUCCAUUUUCACAGCAACAGCAGCAGCAGCAGCAAGCCCAUCCGCAUCAGUUUUCACAGCAACAGCUACAGUUUCCACAGCAACAGUUGCAUCCUCCACAGCAGCUGCAUCGCCCUCAGCAGCAGCUCCAGCCCUUUCAGCAGCAGCAUGCCCUGCAGCAGCAGUUCCAUCAGCUGCAGCAGCACCAGCUCCAGCAGCAGCAGCUUGCCCAGCUCCAGCAGCAGCACAGCCUGCUCCAGCAGCAGCAGCAACAGCAGAUUCAGCAGCAGCAGCUCCAGCGCAUGCACCAGCAGCAGCAGCAGCAGCAGAUGCAAAGUCAGACAGCGCCACACUUGAGUCAGACGUCACAGGCGCUGCAGCAUCAGGUUCCACCUCAGCAGCCCCCGCAGCAGCAGCAGCAACAGCAGCCACCACCAUCGCCUCAGCAGCAUCAGCUUUUUGGACAUGAUCCAGCAGUGGAGAUUCCAGAAGAAGGCUUCUUAUUGGGAUGUGUGUUUGCAAUUGCGGAUUAUCCAGAGCAGAUGUCUGAUAAGCAACUGCUGGCCACCUGGAAAAGGAUAAUCCAGGCACAUGGCGGCACUGUUGACCCCACCUUCACGAGUCGAUGCACGCACCUUCUCUGUGAGAGUCAAGUCAGCAGCGCGUAUGCACAGGCAAUAAGAGAAAGAAAGAGAUGUGUUACUGCACACUGGUUAAACACAGUCUUAAAGAAGAAGAAAAUGGUACCGCCGCACCGAGCCCUUCACUUCCCAGUGGCCUUCCCACCAGGAGGAAAGCCAUGUUCACAGCAUAUUAUUUCUGUGACUGGAUUUGUUGAUAGUGACAGAGAUGACCUAAAAUUAAUGGCUUAUUUGGCAGGUGCCAAAUAUACGGGUUAUCUAUGCCGCAGCAACACAGUCCUCAUCUGUAAAGAACCAACUGGUUUAAAGUAUGAAAAAGCCAAAGAGUGGAGGAUACCCUGUGUCAACGCCCAGUGGCUUGGCGACAUUCUUCUGGGAAACUUUGAGGCACUGAGGCAGAUUCAGUAUAGUCGCUACACGGCAUUCAGUCUGCAGGAUCCAUUUGCCCCUACCCAGCAUUUAGUUUUAAAUCUUUUAGAUGCUUGGAGAGUUCCCUUAAAAGUGUCUGCAGAGUUGUUGAUGAGUAUAAGACUACCUCCCAAACUGAAACAGAAUGAAGUAGCUAAUGUCCAGCCUUCUUCCAAAAGAGCCAGAAUUGAAGACGUACCACCUCCCACUAAAAAGCUAACUCCAGAAUUGACCCCUUUUGUGCUUUUCACUGGAUUCGAGCCUGUCCAGGUUCAACAGUAUAUUAAGAAGCUCUACAUUCUUGGUGGAGAGGUUGCGGAGUCUGCACAGAAGUGCACACACCUCAUUGCCAGCAAAGUGACUCGCACCGUGAAGUUCCUGACGGCGAUUUCUGUCGUGAAGCACAUAGUGACGCCAGAGUGGCUGGAAGAAUGCUUCAGGUGUCAGAAGUUCAUUGAUGAGCAGAACUACAUUCUCCGAGAUGCUGAGGCAGAAGUACUUUUCUCUUUCAGCUUGGAAGAAUCCUUAAAACGGGCACACGUUUCUCCACUCUUUAAGGCAAAAUAUUUUUACAUCACACCUGGAAUCUGCCCAAGUCUUUCCACUAUGAAGGCAAUCGUAGAGUGUGCAGGAGGAAAGGUGUUAUCCAAGCAGCCAUCUUUCCGGAAGCUCAUGGAGCACAAGCAGAACUCGAGUUUGUCGGAAAUAAUUUUAAUAUCCUGUGAAAAUGACCUUCAUUUAUGCCGAGAAUAUUUUGCCAGAGGCAUAGAUGUUCACAAUGCAGAGUUCGUUCUGACUGGAGUGCUCACUCAAACGCUGGACUAUGAAUCAUAUAAGUUUAACUGAUGGCGUCUAGGCUGCCGUGCAUGUCGACUCCUGCGGUGCGGGGCUGGCUGUCUGGCUGGCGAGGAGCUGCUGCGCUUCCUUCACAUGCUCUUGUUUUCCAGCUGCUUUCCUGGGGGAUCAGACUGUGAAGCAGGAAGACAGAUAUAAUAAAUAUACUGCAUCUUUUUAAGAUGUGCAAUUUUAUUCUGAGGAAACAUAAAUUAUGUUUUGUAUUAUAUGACUUUAAGAGCCCACAUUAGGUUUUAUGAUUCAUUUGCCAGGUUUUUAAAUGUUUUCACAAAACUGUUACGGGACUUCAACUAGAAAUAAAAUGGUGUAAAUAAAGACCUUGCUAUCUCUAAAUUAUGGAUGUUAAAGAUUUGAAAUGUUUUGUACUUUGAUUAUUUUUAUUUCUUAUACUCUGUUUUCUUUUAUAUUGAUAUCUUGCCCACAUUUUAAAUAAAUGUACUUUUGAACUUA